AGUCGCGCAGGAGCCCUCAGGCGAGUGGGGGAAGCAUCGCAAGAGACGCGGACCUGGAGCGCGGUCACUGCGUUACCGCAGCGACCUGGGUUACCUAAGCCGGCGGGACUGAGAGGCCGCUGCGCGUGGGCAGGGGCUCAGAUUGCGCCCGCGGUGCCUGUCCCGGCCCCCACCCCGGAACGAUUGCAGCCCUGCGGGGCUCGCCGCCCACACCGCGCUGAGGACGCUGCCCAAGCCAGGCGCCCGCCCCCGCCCGCGGUCUCAGCCGCUCGCAGCGCGCCGCCCCCAGACGCGCGUGGCUGCUGGCGAGGGCUGAGACCGCGCUCCCGCCGGCCAGUUCCCAGCAGCAGCGCAUCCUCCCUGCUCCGCGCCUUCGCUCCGGACCCGCGUCGUCGCAGCCCCGCGGUGAUGAGCCCCGAGCCGGUCCCGCCGCCGCCGCCGCCCCAGUGUCCUGGCUGCGACCGCGCGGAGCCGAUCGCCCAGCGCUUAGAGGAGGGCGACGAGGCCUUCCGCGCGGGCGACUACGAGAUGGCAGCCGAGCUCUUUCGCUCCAUGCUAGCCGGGCUGGCGCAGCCGGACCGCGGCCUGUGCCUGAGGCUGGGGGACGCGCUGGCCCGCGCCGGCCGCCUCCCCGAAGCCCUGGGCGCGUUCCGCGGCGCCGCGCGGCUCGGGGCGCUGCGGCCGGAGGAGCUGGAAGAGCUGGCGGGCGGCCUGGUGCGCGCCGUGGGCCUGCGCGACCGGCCGCUGUCCGCGGAGAACCCGGGCGGCGAGCCCGAGGCGCCCGGCGAGGGAGGGCCGGCCCCGGAGCCCCGCGCGCCCCGCGACCUGCUCGGCUGCCCGCGCUGCCGGCGGCUGCUGCAUAAGCCGGUGACGCUGCCCUGCGGGCUCACAGUCUGCAAGCGCUGCGUGGAGCCAGGGCCCGCGCGGCCGCAGGUGCGGCGCGUGAACGUGGUGCUGAGCGGCCUGCUGGAGAAGUGCUUCCCGGCCGAGUGCCGGCUGCGCAGGCUGGCAGGCCAGGCGCGGAGCCUGCAGCGCCAGCAGCAGCCGGAGGCCGCGCUGCUCAGGUGCGACCAGGCCCUGGAGCUGGAUCAUAGAAAAAUGUGGGAAGAUUUUCAUCUCAUUUAAUAAGCUCCUGAUGAUAAUUCAUUAUUGCUGCUGCGGGCGGAGUUAUAUUUGACCAUGAAGAACUAUGAGCAAGCUCUCCAAGAUGCCAGUGCAGCUUGUCAGAAUGAACCUCUCUUGAUUAAGGGACAUCAAGUAAAAGCUCAGGCUCUUUCUGGAUUGGGAAGAAGUAAGGAAGUGUUAAAGGAAUUUCUCUACUGCCUUGCUCUGAAUCCUGAAUGUAACUCUGUGAAGAAAGAAGCACAGAAGGUAAUGUGUGAAGUGCUGUUUUCAGCUACAGCAAAUGUGCAUGAAAAUUUAACAUCUUCCAUCCAAAGCAGAUUAAAGGCUCAGGGUCACAGCCACAUGAAUGCCCAGGCUCUGCUGGAAGAAGGUGAUGCAGGGAGCUCGGAGAAUUCAUCUGAGAAAUCUGAUAUGCUUGGAAAUACCAAUUCUUCAGUUUUGUAUUUUAUACUGGGUCUACACUUUGAAGAGGAUAAAAAGGCGUUAGAAAGCAUCCUUCCAACAGCACCCAGCGCUGGCUUAAAGAGACAGUUUCCGGAUGACGUGGAGGAUGCACCUGACCUGAACGCCCCUGGAAAAAUUCCCAAGAAAGAUCUCUCACUUCAAAGGAGCCCAAACUCUGAGACAGAAGAAAGUCAGGGGCUCUCGCUUGAUGUAACUGACUUUGAGUGUGCCCUCUGCAUGAGAUUGCUCUUUGAACCUGUCACUACGCCCUGUGGACACACAUUUUGCCUAAAAUGCCUUGAGCGCUGCCUUGACCACGCCCCACACUGUCCUUUGUGCAAAGACAAACUUUCGGAAUUAUUGGCAAGCAGAAACUUUAACAUAACUGUUCUGGCCGAAGAAUUAAUAUUUCGAUAUUUGCCGGAUGAAUUGUCUGAUAGGAAGAGAAUUUAUGAUGAAGAAAUGUCAGAACUGUCAAAUCUGACCAGAGACGUCCCCAUCUUUGUGUGUGCCAUGGCCUUCCCCACGGUCCCAUGUCCACUCCACGUUUUUGAGCCCCGCUAUCGGCUUAUGAUAAGAAGAUGCAUGGAAACUGGCACCAAGCGGUUUGGCAUGUGUUUAUCUGCUGAGCACGCGGGGCUUUCAGAGUAUGGAUGCAUGCUGGAGAUUAAGGACGUGAGAACGUUUCCUGAUGGAAGUUCUGUUGUAGACGCGAUUGGCAUCAGUCGGUUCCGAGUGCUAAGCCACCGCCACAGAGAUGGCUAUAACACAGCGGACAUUGAAUAUCUUGAAGAUGAAAAGGUGGAGGGUCCAGAGUAUGAAGAACUUGCCGCUCUCCACGAUUCUGUGCAUCAACAGUCUGUUUCCUGGUUCGCGUCUCUCCAGGAUCGCAUGAAAGAACAAAUUUUAAGUCAUUUUGGGGUAAUGCCAGACAGAGAACCUGAGCCUCAGAGUAAUCCCAGCGGCCCUGCCUGGUCCUGGUGGAUCCUGGCCGUGCUGCCCCUGGAGCGCAAGGCUCAGCUGGCCAUCCUCGGCAUGACCUCGCUCAAAGAGCGGCUCCUUGCCAUCCGACGGAUAUUAGUCAUCAUCACGCGUAAGAUGAAUAGUCGGCAAGAGCUGGCUAAUGCCAGGGAGAGAAAUAAUUGAUUUUUCUCUCUGUCAAGGUUUCUGGCAGCCCUUGUGCUUUUAUAAAUGUCAGGCAUGGACGAAUAGCCGUCCAUUCAUUGUGCUUCAUCAAGUGCUUGUGGAUGAGGUUCCAAAAUGGGACGCUUGCCAAACAUUGAGUCCUCCUCAAAAAUGACAAUUCUGUGUCUGGUGGGAUCUGACCUUGUGUGAGGUUAGCCUGAAGUCUGAAUGGAGCCCAUAGUUGGAAAACAACCUAAGAAAAUCUCUUAGAAGCAGGUGCUUGGGGAAUGCAGUUCACUGACAGCACAGGACCCUGCAGAUGGUUUACAUGUGGUUUGGGUUUCACGAGAAAGAAGGAUUCACUUCCCAGUCAGCAUCUGGCUCUGCCAGAUGGUAAAGGCGUGCUUUAGUGUGUAGACAAUAUGGGGGAACCACGUUUUUAUCUGGAAGUGGAUUUCUUAGAACACAGGCUAACCAAAACUACGCUUAGGCUUUGCGUGUUGCUGUGAAGUUGUCUGUGAAAUCGAAUAAUCACACCAUUGUUCAGUGCAGGAGCCCAAACUAGUCCUUACCCAAGAAGUAGUAGCCUCUGGAUAGAACUGUGUUUAAUGUCCUGUUGUAGUCCCAGGUGUUGUAAAUUGCAUGUUGUAAUCAAACGAAUGUCAAAACAUAAGAAAGUAUACCUUGGAUAUAGAAAAACCUGAGAACAGUAUCAUUCACUUGAGGAUAUAUAUAUAUAUAUUUACACACAAUAAAGUGAGUUAAAAUUGUAUAUGCAUUGGGAUGUCAAACAUAAAACCACCAAGUGCAAAGAAUGCUUUGAAAGUAGAACCUUGUCUCAUUGAUCAGUGGUUACUAAGCAUUUAGGAAACAGUCAUCUUUUUCUAUUGGGAUUUGCAUUAGAAAUUAGCCCCAUCAGUAAAUUUCAGUUUACUAUCCAUUUAUUAAUAUACAAAAACAUUAAAAAAUCUGCCAUGCCAUGGUAAUCUAUCUAUUCCAGGAAAAUAGAUCAGAAUAUAUGAAGGGAGGAUGGCCGGUAUGGGAUGUAAAUAUUCAGUAAGUUUUUCUCCAACACCAACCUAAAAUUAUCUUUAUUUUUUUGAAAGAAAGUUUUACGGUGAUCAGACCAGGUGUUAUCUGUUAAAGGACAGUAGUAUGACUUCCAUCCUGUAAUGCACGUUGGUGAUAUUGAUUGGAAUAACUGAAUCUGAGAUACUCAUAUGUUCUCUCUGGCCCAACCAGCUGGUGCAUUUGGUUGGCUUCCUCGUCUGUAAGGUGGACAUUCUUAACCAGAGGGUCACGACCACAUCACAGCUGCAAGUUUUGCUUUGUUCAUUGAAGGUGAUUUUUUAGUUUUAAAAUAUAUAUAUCUCAUAAUAUACAAUGUUGAUGGUAUAUCAAUCCAUCAAGCAUUUUAUUAGAAAGACUUUAUAAUAUUAUUAAUUUUUCUUUAGUUUUCAGUAGAUAAAGUAGUUUCAGUAGAUAAAGACUUUAUAAUAUUAUUAAUUUUUCUUUUAGUUUUCAGUCUCAUCAUGGGAGUUAGAAAAUACCAGCAUCACUUAAUUGUAAAGAGAAAAUGUGAAAGUAUUUUCCAAUCCAAUGUUUCAAGUGCCUCACUUAUUGUGAAUCUCAAAUAUCAUCUUGAGAUGGUUUAAUGGCAGUUUGGCCAAGUGAUUUCUAAGAGAUUUUAUUAAUUUAUGCAUUAACAAUAGUAUUCAACUUUCUUAGGCAUUAUAACCUAACCCGAUCAUUUGAUUGGAAUAACUGAAUCAUUCAUUGAUUGGAAUAAAAUAAAGAAAACAAAAUGCAUCUCACAUGCCAGAAGACCUUUACCAGAAGUGGUUCAUGAAAAUCAGUAUGCAUUGACCAUUCUCUGCCUUUCCCUUUUGGAAAAUUUUUUUGUACCUUCAUAUCACAGCUGAAUAGUUAUCAAUGCCAUUUCCAUUUGGAAGUAUCUAAAUAACCACAAUGUGAUCACAGCUUCUCCACGAGCCUUCCUGAAGUAAAGCUGGUAUGCUUGCUAUAAUACUUGGAACCUGUUGCUUUCUCUUCCUCACUCUUUAAAUGUCAUAAGGUCACACAGUUCUUGGAAUCAGAACUAUUCAGUUAUUUCUUCAUGAUUCUGCCUGGCUUUCUGAGUCUUCUCCUUCGGCAUGUUAUGUAAAAGUCUGAACAACAAUGAUGACGCAGACGAGAGCAACAUACGUUUUUAUUUUUUGAUAGGUUUUUAUUUUUUUGAUACCAGAGGGAAUUAACUAUGAUCACAUCGUGCUCUCUCUGUUCAGCAUCACACGCCCACAUACUGCAGUGUGGGAGUAGAUUGGUACUUACUGAGCACUUAGAAACAUCACGCAUCAGGAACCGGGUCAGGGUGACAGCAUCCUACGGUCAUAUCAUGAAGGAAGCCUCCCUUACAAACCUAAAAAAAAAAAACCCCAGCUUCAGUUUGCUACCAAUUAAGCUAAAGCAGAACGGUCUGCUUCCUCCUCCGCCUGCCCCCUUCUGCCUCUUUUCUGUUGGGGAGAUGCCAAUUCUAAGGAUUUCUCAGAAAAUAAUGUAAUCUCUCAUUCAAUGUCAGGACAUUCCAGCUUAAUUGUACUGAAAGUGCUCCAAUAGGCAUGCUCUCGUUACAUUGGAAUCAAAGCAGAAAAGAGUAAUAGCAGCGUGGGGGAGUCAUUUUUCUUCUUGAGGAACAAUACAUGCUGUUCUGUAUUUUUCCAUUCAUCGCCCAAACCUGCCUGUGUCUUUGAAAUGCAAGUAAGAUCCCAAAGGCAGCUUUCUGAAAGCCCGUGGCAUUUUUAGCUUAUCCCAUCCCCCGUGUGUGUCCUCAUCUUCAGAAUUGAAAGUUAGGAUACUUUUUAAAGUUUCAAAAGAAAAUAAUUUAAAAUGUUAAGGUUUAUCCAUAGAAACACAAUAAUUCUUAACCAAUUCAUGUACCAAAUUCAACAGUAUUAUCUCAUUUUUAGGGUCACAAAUGUGUCCUUUUUGCACUUAAACCUCCUCCCUCUCUCAAAAACAAAAACAAACAAACAAACAAAAAACACACCAAGACUGUUUAACAAAUUGUAUCUCAACUCUUAAUAUAUGUUAAGUCUUACCACAGGACAUUUGAAUCAUCAAGGAACAGUUGAAGUUUAUGGAUGGUAGAAUAACAAUGAACUAUGAUAUUAUCACUUUAUUAUAAACUUUUUGGAAAAUUGGCAGUUGCUACCAUCGAAAUACUCCAUUGCCUGUGUUACAUAGAAUUUGUUAUAAUUUUUAAGGGCUUUAAAAAAAUACCCAUCUGUUUCUUCUCCUUCUUGUUUUCUUUUGUGCCCCACCACUUAAAUUACUUGGGUAAAUACCACUCUUCAAAAUUUGAAUACUGUCUAUCAAAUAAGAAGAAGUGUGAAAGAUAUGAAGAAGAAAGGUGAUAGCAAAUUAGAAGAAAAUAAAUGUGGGUGAUUUCUUUUAGUUGAAAGCACAGAGUUUUAUUUUUCCCCAGUAUAACUAUUGAGUAGGGUAGGGAGGUCCCUGUAUCCCCAUUUUUAUUUUUUUUGAGAUGGGGUCUCACUCUGUCACCCAGGCUGGAGUGCAAUGGCGCAAUCUCGUCUCACCACAACCUCCGCCUCCUGGGUUCAAGUGAUUCUCUUGCCUUGGCCCCCUGAGUAGCUGGGAUUACAGGCACGCGCCACCACACCCAGCUAAUUUUUGUAUUUUUUUUUUUUAGUAGAGAUGGGGUUUCACCAUGUUGGUCAGGCUGGUCUCGAACUCCUGACCCCAUGAUCUGCCCGCCUCGGCCUCCCACAGUGCUGGGAUUACAGGCGUGAGCCACCGUGCCCGGCCCAUCUCCCCAUGUUUUAGCAUAGACAGCAGCGGCAUUCAGUGGAAGGAGUUCUUCCCCUUCAACAUCGUCCUUCCCAAAGGCCACAUUCUGAUUCUAUUGUUCACCAAAAACUAAUUCCCAGGGAAGCCCGCUCUGGAUGGGAAGGAUGAGCUGCGUGAGCCAUCGCCCACACAGGGAGAUAACCGAACCCCUUUGCCAGCAUCACCCCCUCUCUACUGGGGUGAGACACUUCAUUCAGAGCACUGGCUCUGACUCCCAGGGGAAAGUCUUUUUCCCUUUACAACUCCUCACCUCAGCCUCACCUUGACUUUCACUUCUCAACUGCUGAAUUCUAUAAAAUAGCCUUUUAGCAGUGACUCAGCUUUUAGGUGAGCACAGAUAAUGAAGAAAUUGAAGUGCCACCAUUGCACUCCCCCAAGUUGGGGACAUAAACUCGAAUUUGCACCCAGGUCUGAUAAAAGUAACUGAUUGAGGACGCAGAAAGGUGGAUGCCAUUGACAGCGUUGACUGUUCUCACAAUUCCUACAGAAAUGAAAGAAGGAGAGGCCCAGCAGACCACACCGGGCCAUGAGGGGAAGCAUGGGAGACAGGCAGAAGCAGGAGUGAGGAGGAACGUGGCUCAGACCCUCUACUGUAUGUUCUGCAGGAAAGGGCAGGGAAAUAGCUAAGACUGGCUGGUCUGAAUAACAGCUCAGACUCUAGGCUAUACAGGUGGUCUCUAGCCAUCUGGCACCUAGCCCCGGGUCGUUAGGGUGGGGGAUAUUGCUUCCUAGGUUGUAAGAGCCAGAUAGAGGAGGAUGGGCUCUGGAUUGGUCACUUUGCUCCCAGGGUAGCCCUUUGCUGUAUCUAAGAAUUGGCUCACCCUGGGAUGGGCAGUUUCUCCUGGGUCAGCGAGGCCCCUGAGAUGUCAAAAUAUCAUAAAAUAUAGAAAUCAUGAUUAAUACAAUUGGUCCUCUGCUGUUUUGACAUACUAAGGUCACUUUUGAUAGCAGAAACUUUUAAAGAGUAGGGCAUACGUUGCCCUGAAGAGCAUAGAAAACAUUUUAUUCUGAGAGUAGAAAGGAGGAAGACACGUGGAGAUACAGGAGUCCCUUAGGCUGGCCCAUAGCUGAGUCUCUCAUGUGUGUGGCAUUAGUCAAGAAUGUAGUUCUGCAGUUUGCGGGGGGGGGGUCUCUAACAUUUCUUGGUGCAGUUGUUAACAUGUGUUAAACAUAUGAGUCUGAUGAUGAUAUCGCGGUGUUUCUCGGCUCGGGGUGGCAGGUCUGGCGGUUGUGUGGCUGGGGGUGUGCACUGAUAGUUCAGUAAAGGAUAAGUAGAGACUCGUGGUGUUCAUGUGUCACCACAGGGAGGGAGUGGCUGUGGAGACCCAGGACAGGAAGUCGCGGUGGAAAGCAGGCUGGGGUGGUAGGAGAAGGCACCGGGGGUGGGUGCUCCUCCCCCAGGGGUUGAGGAGUUGACUGAUAGGGGGCAGUUACCUCCUGGGAAAGCAAGACGCUCCCUUAAGUUUUAGAAUGGUACAGAGAGUAGUCCCUUCUACCAGAGUUUCCAUUUAGACAUGGGAGUGUAGGGGGCCAUGUUUCGGCAGAAGCAGGGCAUGUAUCAGCAUUAGUGGACUCCUCAGUAUUAAAAGGAAGAACAGCAAACAUGUCAUGUGCCCACUUUGUGCCUCAGGAGAGGUAGCCCGUGGACAUCGCUAGGGCAGAGGUUUUAAUAUCUGGGACAAAGUUAUCUCCCACGGCGAGGUCGUGGCUGGGACCAUGUCAUCUUCAGCCGUGAGCUGCUGGGCUGGGCAAUGUCUUCUGGGAUGUGAGACGUGGGGUCUCCUUUCUAAGCGGACCCCCACUCGUGCUGAUGUGGGUCCCAGCAUUUGCCGCGUUUGGUUGAAACAGUGGCUUACCUGGAGGGUCUGGGUCUCUGGAUCAUAAACCAGCGAAAGCCCCCACAUCAGUGGUGACAAGAUCAAUAGACCCCAGAAUGUGUGCAGCUGUGCUUGAUAGGGUUUUGGUUCUUGCUUUUUGGUGGAAGUUUAGGCUCAAGUGGGUCCCGUAUCGGAUGAGCAGCUGCACGGCCUGUGGGAGCCCUGGGGUUAGUGGGUCCAGGAGAGAAUGUGUUCUCUCUCUGGGCUCCAGCCCUGAUGGGGUGGGGAUAAGAUGCAAGAUUUAUAGGAAUAGGGGGAAACAUUAUGGAAGGCCCCAAUAUGUAAUGAGCUUUUAUAUACAAGAAUGCAAGACAUAGCCCUCUUUUUAUGUUUAAAGGGGACUAUGGUAAUGUUUUUUAAAGUUUGUGUGAGGUGUGAGUCAACCGAAAGGCCCUAAAUUAAGAGAGAUUCAGGUUUGUGGUGCAAGAUAGAGGCCCAUUUCGGGGUCUGUUUGCAGACCAGAAUUUGAAAUGGAGUUGUUUGAGGAGACCAUUGUGUGUCUUCGUGAAACCGAUUGUGUGGAACCUAUCAGGGCUGUGGAAGUUGUAGCGAAUGCCUUUUCCCAGAGCCCAGCAUUGUGGAUUCCGAGAAGUGGCAUGUGUGUCUCAGUGACUUCCAGUGAUGCCUGCCACUCUGAAGAGAUGAAGGAGUGUCCUGGCAAGACCUGGAAUCCCAGCUGUAGCACCUGUGGAGAGAUGUGAUUUAGAUUUGGAUUUGGGGUAUCUGUGAGGAAGAGUCCCAGAGUUUUUCAUCCUGAAGGGGGCAACUCUUGGGCAGUGGUCCAACAGUUGGCCAUAAAUGUGAAGCUGGGGCGCUGUGCUGACCAGGGCAUCCAGCGUUAAGACGACUGCCUAACUUUGGCCACAUGCGUUGUUUUUUGGGUUCCGUUUCGUAUCAGGGCAUGCUGGCUAAAAGAUGGGAAGCAGCAACAUUCUCUUGGGCUCCAUCAUUUAUAUGAGGGUUGGCAAUGCCAUCUGUACCCUCUGUGAACUCCCACUGCUGUUCACUCAGUUAAUCUAAGGGACACCAAGGGGUCUGCGGGAGGAUGACCUCACAAGGGACUGAGGACAUGGGAGACCACCCUCCUGUGGGUAGAAUACACCAGAGGGCCCAGGCUUGACUCUGUCCUGUGUUAAGGAGGCAUCGGUAGUUUUGCUGAGCUUGUCAGGUGUUUAUAAUGGACAGUUGGAGAUUGGGGUCCUAGGCUUAGGUCUUUGAGAGCCUCUGUGUCCAGGAGAGCCCAGUAGGCAUCCAGCCAUUUACUGCUUUAAUAGGGUAGCAUGAGGCUGAGAGGGAUAGUUUCUUGCAUCCAAAGCCCUUAGGCACCUUAUGUCCAUCCUAAGUGGGCCAGAGACUCCAGGGCUGCAUAGAGCUUGCCAGAGCUUCUAUAAUGAAGGGGUCUCUGAGGGCACCAACAGGAGUGCCCAUGGAUUUUAAGGUUUGAUUAUAGAGGUUGUUUAUGGAGGGUGCCCCAUUUAAAGCAAGCUGAUUUGUAAGCAGCAGCAAGAAGAUUAAGUAAAAUUUGUAAAUGAGGACUACAUUGCCAUCAGAACCUCGAAAGUAUCUAAAGAUGUUGGACUUGUAUGUCCUUAAUGAGUGUGACAAUGAGUUUCCUCAUUUGUGCUCCUGGAGAAGGCGGAUGUGGUGAAGACCCUGUCUGCAGACAUUGUGUGCCAUGGCAAAGCCGUGGAGCUCCCUGUGGGUGGCCUGCAAAGGUGUAUGUGCCCCUCAGGGCAGAAGGCAAACGGCAGCCAAGAAGCUGUGCAAGUAGACACUUAAUGGGACAUGUUAGCCAAAUCUGUAAGAGCAAAAUAUUGGCCAGUUAUUUAUUGUGUAGAAUUAAUAAUUUUAAUAAUAAUGGAAAUUGGGUAAUGGAUGGGACUGCAGCAAUAAGGUUGUAGUAAUCCACCAUGAGGCACACUUGUUUUUUUCCAGGUUUAAGGAUAGGAAAGAUUGGGCUGUUCAAUGGAGAAACAAGGGUAUAAUCACCCCUUUAUUAAUUAGUAAGUUUUAAUCCUUGAAUACCUCAUAUUAACUGUUUUAACUGGAGGUCCAUGGGGCAUCAUUUUAUCAAGCUAGUUUAUAACUGCCAAAGACUGACUUUAAUUUUAAUUUAUUAUUUGUUUUAUUAGAGUGUCUGUGUUCAAUAUGGGAUAUUAGGGCGUUGGGUACUAUGACCACAGGAAAUUUAGACAGGCUACAGUUAAAGUGAAGCAUACCUUACCCAUCCACCCCCCAUUUUAUAUUUAGUUGCCUUUUUAAAAAGAUUAUAGGGGUACAAUGUUUAGAUUUAGUGGGAUCUCCAGGUAUAACUGUAAUUUGAGCCCCAGUGUUAAGACUAUGAAGCUUUGUCAAUGGGUACAUUUUAGCAAAUGUUACAAUUAAUUUAGAACCUAAGUUAUGGAGACACAAAAGCCAAUAGGCACCCUUUUAUGUUUUGGUUAAAUGUUUCAGUAUAUACAUCUUAUUUAUUUGUAAUAUUAGUAUAUAAUUUGUUGUAUACAUUUUUAGUGUAUAAGCGUUGGAUUUCUAAUUGGAUCAGAUUAGGGACCUUCCGUUUAGCUGCAUAUGUACAUAUACAUGUACAAUUUAUUAUAUAUUUGCGUUAAAAUAGCCUAUCUGCAUGUGUAUAUAUGUGUGUAUGUGUAUGUAUAUGCACUCACACGCAUAAAUACACAGUCUAUUUAGUUACCUUUAAUGUUUUUUCCCUUGUACCUAGGCUUUUUCUCGCUUUUUCCUUUUUUUCUGAUUUUGUGGCAAUUUAGUUGGAAGGAGGCGGUCCCAGCAUGUUGACAGGCAGGGUGUUCAGAGUGCCCAGGCACACUGGUGGGGGGUGGUUACAGGCUCACGUAGCUCAGGGGCUUCUGCAGGUCUCAGGGGAGUGGGAACAAAGUGUCCCACCCCUUCCCCUUUUCCUCAAACCUCAAGCCACUGGUCUCUAUGGAUAGAUCCUUUGCAUCCCACCGGAUUGAGGAAUGAGUCACAACAGCUGCAAGGCUCUUAAAGCAACAUUUAAACCUUUUGGCGGCUGUCAUUUCUGUGAGGAGGGUGCCUCUCACCGGCCGCAUGGCCGGAGGAUCCCUGCAGCGCUUUGGAGACCAACACCCAGAUCCUUUGCCCAGGAGUGCGAUUAAUUCCUCACUGGAUGCUGGGGGAGGGCCCCUCAGGUGAGCAGCCCACCACUGACUUCAGCGUUGCUGGCUCGGUUAUCAGACUCUCAUCCAACACAAGCUCACAGGGAAAGCCGUUCCUUGCUCCUUGUGGAGGGAGCUACCGUCAUUGCCCUGAGACCACCAGCCAAGAAAGUAGGUAUGUCCAGGUAGGGAAUUCAGAGGGACCCAGUGCAUCCAAUUAUACAAUUAUACCCAGAAGGUCCUGUGUAGGGGACUGCGAUUGACAUCACCCUAGUCUGCAGCACCAAGGACUGAAUGAGCUCAGUCCUCUUAUAAUUUAGGCUGGACUGUCACAGACACUGGCAGACACAGCAUACGUGGUGCAGCCAAAGUGCAAACAUGCCAGCAGCGGCCAUGCUCCCCAGGGUGGGGGUCCAGUUAGUAAGCCACGCGCAGCCAAGAGGCGAGGCAUGCCCUGUGCCACACACGGACUCACCCUGCUCACUGUGCCCGUGGUAUCGAAAUGUACCCACGUUUAAUUCAUAAAGGAGAGGCUGCUGUCAUUGAAAGAAAAGUUUGUUACUUGCAUUUCUGGAGAAAAGGAGCGCACCAGGCCACGCAGGGCCACAGGAGGAGGACGCACCAGAGUGGUCAGGAGGCAGAACUAGGCGAGCAGCUUUCCACUGUGUCUCCAUGGCAAAGGCGAAGAUGGGCGGGGGCAGAGUGUAGGAUUGGCAGGUUUGAAUGUCUUGGGCAGUAGCUACAGGGGUGGUCUCCAGCUGCCUGGUGCCUGGCCCUGGGUGAUCAGGGUGAGGGGAUACUGCCUUCUGCAGUGGAAGAGUCAAAUCGAGGAGAUGGACUCUGAGUUGGUUAGUGUGCAAAGGUGCACUCCCAAGGGACCCCUUUGCUAUCUCUAAGAAUUGGCCUGCCCUGGGAAGGGCAGUCUCUCCCCAGUCAGUGAGGUCCCCAAGAUGUGAAAACAUUAUACAUUAUAAAAAAGCAUGAUUAAUAUAAGCUCAUUCUAGCAUUUCAGGUUACAGCUUCUAGAAGAGGUUUGUAGUCUCAAAUGAGUAGGUUUUUCCUCUAGAGAGGGGCGGGCCUGGACCUUCAAGCACCCCUUGGUGUGUUUAGGAGCUCAGGAGCAGAAGCACCUGCCUGCAGCCCUGCAGCUAAGGAAGUUCUCUCAGUCACUCAGAGCAGGGAGGGGCUGAGAGAGUCAUGUGAGGCUCCCGGGGUACUACGACAGCCCUCGAGGUGAAGGAUUGGCCCUGAUCAUAAUAGAGAACCCUGAGGAAGUUUACUGUCAUGAGUCUCGGCUGGUUGGCGCAUGUGACCUUUGAAGGAUGAAGAUGGAGUUUGCAACAUGAGUAUCUCUAACCUUUUGCUUUUCAGGGAUCAUUUUCAAAAAUUGCAUUGGGGCCUUCGUUAUUUACCAUAGUAUUUUCACUUUCAUAGUUUUGUCACCUUUUUGUACUGUGAACAGUUCAACCAGUGACCGACUUCUCUCUCAUGCUGUUUACCCCACACACAAUUUCCCACUCAAUUCUGAAAAUAAGAACCUGUUAAUAGGUUGGAAAGCUGUGUACUCUAUUCAUAUAUUGUUCUUUCAUGCUAGUGGAGAGUGGUGUCAUUAGCAUCUUAAUUUUAGAGUUGUGAAAUGAUUUUACCAAUUAGGAAUUGAAUGUGUAUUUUUUUUCUGUUUAAUAAGAAGAGCAAAUUUGAAUAAAUAAGCUGGUGUAGAUAAACUUAAUAAUCAUGCUUUUUCUUGUUUGGAGAUAGGUGAUGUGUUGUCAUAUCCUGUGAUACAGGUCACUCAUCUGGCCUUCUGUUUCUGAAGUUUAAGUCUGGUUUGAAUAUGUAAUAAUACUACUCAGCAUUUCUUGUUGCCUAAGUGAGACGAAACUUAAAUGUUAUGAUAUUUACUUCAUGUAUUCUUGUACUGUUCAUUUCAAUUAAUUGGUAUUGUAUAUCUAAUAUGUGAUAUUUGAACUGAAUAAAACUUACAGUGUUGUAAAUGUUCUUUAAUAAAUAAUCACACCUAAGUAAUAGGCUAGACUGAUGAGAAAUUAGAUCAAAUCAGUGCCUAGGCCUUUGUGUUUGUGUCGUAGGGAUGUACUAACACAUCACCACAGACUGACGGCUUUUCACAAUAAAUCAGUUUUCUUCGCUCACAUUUCUGGACAUUAGAAAUCCAAAGCCAAGGUGCCAGUAGGGCCGGGCUUUCUCUGAAGGCCCCAGGAAAACUCCUCCUUCAUCUCCUCCAGCUGGUGUGGCUGCUGGCCGACCUCGGCCUUCCUCGGCCAGCGGCUGCAUCACUCCAGUUUCCGUGUCCAUCGUCACAUGGCCUUCUUCCCUCUGUGUGUCUGUGUCCAGAUAUCCCUUUCCUUAUAUAAGGACACCAGUCAUUAGAUUUAACUUCCACCCUAAUCCAGGAUGACCUCAUCUUAACUUGAUUACAUCUGCAAAGACUGUAUUUCCAAAUAAGGUUAUAUCCACAGGUUCUAGUGGACAUGAAUUUUAGAGGAACAGUAUUCAACACAGUGCAGAUGUGGAACGAUUCCAAUUUAAUUUUAGUAGGAAAAAAAAGGAAAGAGGGCUGCCAAUGGCUUUGGCUUAAAACCAUAAUUACUUUUAAAAAUCAUUUCUAUCCAAGGCAGAUAAGAUUUAAUAAGAACUGAAGCUUGUAUAGUUGUUUAUUUGGGAGGAAGGGGGUAGUGCUUCUUAAGAAAAGGAAUAUGAAUUGCAAAUACUGAGUUAACUAUGAAAGCAUAUAUUUAUUUGGAAUUUUUAGAGGCAUAAAUUACAAUAUUUAAAACAGCAUAACACUCUACAAAAUACUGAAAAGUAUUUUUAUUAACUUCCUGGCACCUUUAUGAUACCUUUCCCAUCUUUUUUUUUCUUUUUUUUAACCUACAUACUCUGGUUAGUUUGUUUGUUUAUUUAUUUAUUUAUUUUCUUCUUGGGGGACAUGGUCUUGCUGUGUCAUCCAGGCUGGAGGGCAGUGGUACAAGCAUAGCUCACUGCAGCCUCAACCUCUUGGGUUCAAAGGAUUGUCCUGCCUCAACCUUCUGAGUAGCUGGGACCACAGGUGCAUGCCGCUAUACCCGGCUAAUUUUUUUACUUUCUAUGGAGACGAGGUCUAGCUGUGUUGCCCAAGCUGGUCUCAAAUUCCUGGGCUCAAGCAGUUCUCCCACCUUGGCCUCCCAAAGUGUGAGAUUGCAGGCAUAAGCCACUGCACCUAACCCUGCAUACUCUUUGAUCAUCUUUUUCUUCUUAGGACAAUCUUGUGUUGGUUACUAAAGAGAGAAUGAUAUUUAAGUUCUUCCUCUAACAUGGAUAUGGGGCAAAAAUCAUAGACUAAAAGUUUCAGUUUUCACAAGUCAUUAUUGGUAAUGUCAUUUAAAUAGGAUGGUUGUCAAAUCUGGGAAAACCUCUGAUGAAGUCUUUUAUAUGUGAGUUGUAAGGAUCAGGCAUUUUCCCGCUUCCUCAUGCAGUGACUAAUCUUAACUCCUUCAGCACUGUUGGAUGAAACUUUCUGUGAUGACGGACAUUGUUGGAAAUAAAGCUCGGAGUCAUAAGGAAAAUGA